AGCCUCUGGGAAGGCCCAGCAUGGAGGCAGCCACAGCUCCGGAGGUGGCCGCAGGAUCCAAGCUGAAGGUGAAAGAAGCCAGCCCAGCGGAUGCUGAACCACCCCAGGCUUCACCUGGACAGGGGGCUGGCAGCCCCACUCCCCAGCUCCUGCCCCCUAUAGAAGAGCACCCCAAGAUCUGGCUACCUCGGGCCCUGAGGCAGACCUACAUCCGGAAGGUUGGGGACACAGUGAACCUACUAAUCCCAUUCCAGGGCAAGCCCAAACCUCAAGCCAUCUGGACACAUGAUGGCUGUGCCUUGGACACCAGGCGUGUGAGUGUGCGGAAUGGGGAGCAAGACUCCAUCCUCUUCAUCCGAGAAGCCCAACGUGCUGACUCAGGUCGCUACCAACUCCGCGUGCAGCUGGGUGGGCUGGAGGCCACCGCCACCAUUGACAUCCUGGUGAUUGAGAGGCCAGGCCCUCCUCAGAGUAUUAAGCUGGUGGACGUUUGGGGCUUCAGCGCUACACUGGAAUGGACACCGCCCCAAGAUACGGGGAAUACAGCACUUCUGGGAUACACGGUGCAGAAGGCUGACACAAAAUCCGGGCUGUGGUUCACGGUGCUGGAGCACUAUCACCGCACCAGCUGCAUCGUCUCUGACCUCAUCAUCGGCAACUCCUAUGCCUUCCGUGUCUUUGCUGAAAACCAGUGCGGACUCAGUGAAACAGCCCCCAUCACUACGGACCUCGCCCACAUCCAGAAAGCAGCUACUGUUUACAAGACCAAGGGGUUUGCCCAACGAGACUUCUCUGAAGCCCCAAAGUUUACCCAGCCUCUGGCCGACUGCACUACAGUCACCGGCUAUAAUACCCAGCUCUUCUGCUGUGUCCGCGCCUCUCCCCGGCCCAAGAUCAUCUGGCUGAAGAACAAGAUGGAUAUCCAAGGCAACCCUAAGUACAGAGCCCUGACUCACCUGGGAAUCUGCUCCCUAGAGAUCCGCAAGCCGGGUCCCUUUGAUGGAGGCAUCUAUACCUGCAAGGCGGUGAACCCCCUAGGGGAGGCAUCUGUGGACUGUCGGGUGGAUGUGAAAGUUCCUAAUUGAGGACACCUAAGAAGGCAUGGUACUCUGACAAAGGUGUGUGGUCCCAAGCAGCACAUUAUUGGCAAAAGACAGCUCAGCUCAUCAUUUAGAACCGGACAGCUCUUUUAGAUUUUCCGUCAUUCACAUUAGCUAUGUUGUGAACAAAGUGAUGCAUAAGGCGAAAAAGAAGCUUGAGACAGAACUAAAGAGAACAAGUUCCCAGUGUCCUCUCUGACUUGUAGCUGCUGGCUGAUGGAAAUUGGAAAUGAAUUUGAUCCCAUAAGACAUUUAUUUAAGGCUCUCACUGGUAUGUAGCAAAUGAAAGCCUAAAGGGGUGCGUUACAAGUACAGACUUCUCAGGAAAGCGCUCUCCGACAGUCGGCUUGCAGAGACAACUCUCCCUCCCUCACCUCCCUCUCUGUGUUAAUGAUACUUGUGUUCGUGUUAGUUGCCCCUUUCCCUCUCUCACAGCCAGUGCCCAGCAAUGAAGUGAAUUCAUGGCACAGGAGCCAGGGACCGUGACAACGGUGCCCUCAGCAGCCUGGUGUCCUCUGGCCAUUUGCUGUCAUGGCUACAAAGUGCUCCCUCUUUUCAGUGCCUCCAGGAAGCCCGCCAGUGGUGAGACUGUGUCCUCAAGGAGCUUCGGCACCAUGUCUGGUUUGGAUUCAUCUAAAUAAAUAUGUGGUUCCCCAGUG